UAAUUUUACACUUCAGUUAUUUUAUGAGAAUAUUUUAUCUUCAAAUAGAAAUUUGCCUACAAGUUUUAUAUUUCCCCUGGAGUUGUUCGAUGAAUUUGUUAGGUAGUUGCUUAAACUUUUUGAGAAAACUUUUUCUCAGGUUUAUGAAUUUUUAGGUUACAAAAUAAGACCCUCUUUUCAUUAAUUCAUUCAAAGUAGCUGAGUCAUAGUUAGAGUAUACUGGUUAAGCGUGUGUGGCCUCCAUUGUCAGAUGACUGGGCUAUAUCCCACUCUCCACUGCCCACUAGAUAUGUGGGCUUAGGAAAGCAGUCAAGACAGUGCAGGAGGUGAGGCCAUCUUAUAGGAAGAGCAGUUGUCCAGCCUCUGGAAGAAAAAGCUCAGUGGAGAUCUGACAGCCUUCCUGGGGGAUAUUAACAGGGCUCCUGUGUUGCAGAGGAACACUACUUUCUCAGUGUAGCUCUGAGAAAGAGAACCAGAAAAAGGAUUUCUCUUCAGUAGAAAAGGCAAAUACCAUAAAGAAGGAAUCGCUGUAACUUAUUGCUUGGACCACUGACAGCAGCUGUUUGCAAUAGUUGACAAGGAGAAGGAAUAGAGGGAAAAGAUAGAGAAAAGAAGAGAUUUUGUUUCCUCUCAGAAAACCAAUGGUCCAAGUGAAAACACAAACACAAGAAUGGAUACUAAUGAUGACCCUGAUGAAGACCAUCUUACAAGUUAUGAUAUUCAGCUAAGUAUUCAAGAAUCCAUUGAAGCCAGCAAGACUGCACUUUGUCCUGAAAGAUUUGUACCCCUAAGUGCUCAAAACAGAAAACUUGUGGAGGCCAUAAAACAAGGUCACAUUCCUGAGCUCCAGGAGUAUGUAAAAUAUAAAUAUGCAAUGGAUGAAGCUGAUGAAAAAGGAUGGUUUCCAUUGCAUGAAGCUGUUGUUCAACCCAUUCAACAAAUACUUGAGAUUGUUCUGGAUGCAUCCUAUAAGACACUCUGGGAAUUCAAGACCUGUGAUGGAGAAACACCCUUGACUUUGGCAGUCAAAGCUGGUCUGGUGGAAAAUGUAAGAACUUUAUUAGAAAAGGGAGUGUGGCCCAACACAAAAAAUGAUAAAGGAGAGACCCCCCUUCUGAUUGCUGUGAAAAAGGGCUCCUAUGACAUGGUGUCGACUCUGAUCAAACAUAACACUAGCCUAGACCAGCCCUGUGUCAAGCGAUGGUCAGCAAUGCAUGAAGCAGCCAAGCAAGGCCGAAAAGAUAUCGUAGCUCUGCUGCUGAAACAUGGAGGCAAUGUCCACCUGAGAGAUGGAUUUGGAGUCACACCACUAGGCGUCGCUGCCGAGUAUGGUCACUGUGACGUGUUAGAACAUCUAAUCCACAAAGGUGGUGAUGUGCUUGCUUUGGCGGAUGAUGGGGCGUCGGUGCUGUUUGAGGCAGCAGGAGGUGGCAAUCCCGACUGCAUUUCCCUCCUGCUGGAAUAUGGAGGAAGCGGAAAUGUACCUAACCGAGCAGGACAUCUUCCUAUACACCGAGCUGCCUAUGAGGGGCAUUAUCUUGCACUGAAAUAUCUUAUCCCAGUAACAUCUAAAAAUGCAAUUCGGAAAAGUGGGCUAACACCAAUUCACUCAGCAGCAGAUGGACAAAAUGCACAGUGUCUAGAACUGCUCAUUGAAAAUGGUUUUGAUGUCAACACUCUACUUGCUGACCACAUUUCCCAGAGCUAUGACGAUGAGAGGAAGACUGCGCUGUAUUUUGGCGUUUCUAAUAAUGACGUUCAUUGCACAGAAGUCCUUCUGGCUGCAGGUGCAGACCCAAACUUAGAUCCCCUCAACUGUCUACUUGUUGCAGUGAGGGCCAAUAAUUAUGAAAUUGUCAGGCUGCUUCUCUCCCAUGGAGCUAAUGUCAAUUGUUAUUUUAUGCAUGUGAAUGACACUCGUUUCCCCAGUGUCAUUCAAUAUGCUCUAAACGACGAGGUAAUGCUGAGGCUAUUGCUGAAUAAUGGCUAUCAAGUGGAGAUGUGCUUUGACUGCAUGCAUGGUGACAUCUUUGGAAAUUCAUUUGUGUGGUCAGAGAUACAGGAAGAGGUGCUGCCAGGAUGGACAUCUUGUGUAAUAAAAGAUAACCCGUUCUGUGAGUUUAUUACAGUUCCUUGGAUGAAGCACUUGGUAGGCAGAGUUACUCGUGUACUAAUAGAUUACAUGGAUUAUGUUCCUCUGUGUGCUAAACUGAAGUCUGCACUAGAAGUACAGAGAGAAUGGCCAGAAAUCCGCCAAAUACUAGAGAAUCCUUGUUCAUUGAAGCAUUUGUGUCGGUUAAAAAUUCGAAGGCUUAUGGGUCUCCAGAAACUCUGCCAGCCAGCCUCAGUGGAGAAGCUUCCUCUACCACCAGCUAUUCAAAGAUACAUAUUAUUUAAAGAGUAUGAUCUCUAUGGACAAGAGCUAAAAUUGACAUAACUUAAUAUUUUAAAAUGUGAUUUAAAAAAAAUGUUGAAAUGUGAUUCCCUCAGAUAAUUUCUUGUAACCAUUUUACAUCCUUAAUUGUAAAGUGUAUUUAAAUUCAUUGACAGUUUUAUAGGUUAUCAUGUGUUCUUAUGGGAACACCAUGAUUUAUGUCUUUAAAGACAUUUGCAUUUUUUAAAGAUAGUAUUUUGAACUUAGAUUUGUAUCUUUGUUUGCUACAAGUCAUCAAACUCUCCCUAUCAAGUGGCUCCUACAAUAUCCACAAUCAAGUCUCUAUGUUUAAAAAACAGAUAACCACUUUCUCAAACCCACAUCUGCCAGUUGCUGGCCAGAUUCUCCUGUCUUUCACGGUCUUGCUGUGUAAAAGAGCUCCUCCUGCCUGUAAGUUCACAGACUGUGAUCUGGCAUCUGACCCUCCACUGCUUUUCUCAAGGUCCCUGACAAUCUCUUUGUUGGUAAAUUCAGUGAACAUUCUUCAGUCCCUCUUCCAAUCGAUUCCUACAGCAUCUAACAUUGUUGCCUGUUCCUUGCUUGAAAUGAUAUCUCUUUCCUUGUUUCUCGCAAAACCUGUUCUCUUGGGUGUCCUCCCACCUCCCUGGACACUCUGUCUCUGGCUUCUUUCUGCCUAGCUCAUCUCUAGCCAAUCUUACAGUUAUAUAUCUUAAGCCCUCUUCUCUUUGUUCUUUAAGUUAUAUAUCCUAAGCCCUCUUUGCUUUGUUCUCUGGGAUAUUUUAUCCACAUCCAUGGUCUUAAUCAUUUUGCUAGAGACUACAAAAUUUCCAUCCAAAGCUCAGCUCUUUCUCUCAUGUUCUCCUGACCUAUGUAGACAAUUGGCCUCAUGAACAUUUGAACACAAAGACACCUCAAAUUCAACAUGUCCCCAGAUGAACUAAAAAAAAAAAAAAAAAAAAAACCUCUUUCCCGAGCUCAGUAGUUAGCACAAUGCUCAAUUCAGUUUCCAAAGAAAAAAGCCUGGACAUUAGGUUUGACCAUCCCAUUUUCCUCACCCAAUAAGACAAAUCACCAAAUCCUAUUAAGUUUAUCUCCUGAAGUCAUCUUCCACUCAGCAGCCCCCCACCACCCACCCCGCAUUUGGCCCUAAGUCUAUUAUCUUCUUUUUCCUGGGAUAAUACAAUGCUGCUUAUCUGGCUCCCCUGACUCUGUCUUGCCCUGUCCCAAACACUUUCUACAUACAGCAUCUCAGAAGAGUCUUUUACAAAUAUAAUAGAGUUUCACUUCUCUGCUUAAGAUCAUUCCCAUUGCUCUUAAAUUCCAAAGUUCUUACUUGAACUUUCAUGAUCUAACUCCUGCCUUCUUCUUUAGCCUCAUCUCUGGAUGUCUACCUUUCCUCCUUUCCCUUGAACCUUCUAGAAUUUUAUUUUUUAAACACUGAUUCCCAGACUUCAAGGUGUCAUACACUAAUAGGUUUUAUUGUGUUUAUUUUUCAAAAAGAGUCAUUAAAAAAUACCAUCUACUAUCACCAUCAUUUCAUAAAAGAGGGGUCAUUUUAAUGCCAGAAAGUAAGAUGGUCAUAAAUUCAGUCAUUCAAGUUGAAUGACUUUUACCUUGAAAAGACCUCACACUGCUCUCAUUUCCCCAUUGACGAGUGAGAAUUUCACUGUGGGCCAUCAAAUAUCUGAGGACCUUUGUAUGGGGAACCUCUGCUGUAGAAUAGACCAUGCUCUCUUUUAACCUCAGGGUCUUCGCAUUUCCUUCUCUCAUCUGGAACUCUCUUUCCGCUUUUUUUGCACCCUUUCACCUGAUCAACUCCCACUUACCCUAUAGGUCUCAGCUGAGAUGUUGCUUCCUCUAGGAUGGGAAGCCUCAGCACAGAACUUGUCAUGCCAUAUUAUAGAUGCCUGUGUUCCCUGCUGUCUUCCCACUAGACUAUAAGCUCUAUGAGGGUAGGUUCUAUGUUUGUUUUGUUUUCCAGUGCUUUCUCAGGGCCAAACACAUUCCCUAGAGCAUGGAGUUCAAUAAUUGUUUGUUGAAAUAUAUUGAAUAAGUGACAAAAAUAAUCAGUGACAUCAUGGUGAAAUAAUAGUUUUAAAUUUCUGAGUGAGUUAUGUAAUCUUGUAAUUAUUUAAUGCUAUUAUUCUUAGAUUUUAAUAGUGUAUUUUUCUUAUAUUUAUUUUUACCUUGUUACCGUAUUCUUUAAACAGUAAUAUCUCACUGGUCUGUAAAGUUUUCAAGUUGUAUUUAGCUUUAGUUACCUUUGAAAGAUAAAUAAGUAUGAAAAAAAUCGUACAAUUAGGGCUAUAAUUUUAACUUCUUGUAUUCCCUAGAGGAUAUAUUUUAUAUGUAAGUUAAACUGUAAUGUAUUUAUAUUUAAUUGCAACAUCUUGUAUACAAGAUUUUAUUAUUCUUGUGUUGCACUCUUAGACGUGGUUAAAUGUAUUGUUACCUAAAAAUAUUACUCUAAUGAAUAAAAAAUCAUAUUGAGGUUAUAAGUCUGCUUUAUGAUACUUCAUAUAUUAAACUUUUGCUCACUAAA